GCACCGGAAGCCGACUCAACAGAGCUAUGGCGGGUUUGACUGUGAGAGACCCAGCGGUGGAUCGUUCUCUACGUUCUGUGUUCGUGGGGAACAUUCCUUAUGAAGCUACUGAAGAGCAGUUGAAGGACAUCUUUUCUGAGGUUGGACCUGUUGUUAGUUUCAGAUUGGUAUACGAUAGAGAGACAGGAAAGCCAAAGGGUUAUGGCUUCUGUGAAUACCAAGACCAAGAGACAGCACUUAGUGCCAUGCGGAACCUGAAUGGGCGCGAAUUCAGUGGGAGAGCACUUCGAGUGGACAAUGCUGCCAGUGAAAAGAACAAAGAAGAGCUGAAGAGCCUUGGCACUGGUGCCCCUGUCAUUGAGUCACCUUAUGGAGAGACCAUCAGUCCUGAGGAUGCCCCUGAGUCCAUUAGCAAAGCAGUUGCCAGCCUUCCACCAGAGCAGAUGUUUGAGCUGAUGAAACAAAUGAAGCUCUGUGUCCAGAAUAGUCCCCAGGAGGCACGGAACAUGUUACUUCAGAACCCUCAACUGGCUUAUGCUUUGCUGCAAGCACAGGUAGUGAUGAGAAUUGUGGAUCCGGAAAUUGCCCUGAAAAUUCUGCAUCGCCAGACAAAUAUCCCAACGCUGAUUGCAGGCAACCCUCAGCCAGUCCAUGGUGCUGGGCCUGGCUCAGGAUCCAAUGUGUCAAUGAACCAGCAGAAUCCUCAGGCCCCUCAGGCCCAGUCUUUGGGUGGAAUGCAUGUCAAUGGCGCACCUCCUCUGAUGCAAGCUUCUAUGCAGGGUGGAGUUCCAGCACCAGGGCAAAUGCCAGCUGCUGUCACAGGACCUGGCCCUGGUUCCUUAGCUCCUGGAGGAGGAAUGCAGGCUCAGGUUGGAAUGCCAGGAAGUGGACCAGUGUCCAUGGAACGGGGGCAAGGAACCCUACAGCACUCGCCCGUGGGACCCGCCGGGCCUGCAUCAAUUGAGCGAGUUCAAGUGCCGAUGCAAGACCCCAGAGCAGCUAUGCAGCGGGGAUCCUUGCCUGCGAAUGUCCCAACCCCUCGAGGCUUGUUAGGAGAUGCUCCGAAUGAUCCACGGGGAGGCACUUUACUUUCUGUAACUGGAGAGGUAGAGCCUAGAGGUUACUUGGGACCACCUCAUCAGGGUCCACCCAUGCACCAUGUCCCUGGCCAUGAGAGCCGAGGACCACCCCCACAUGAACUGAGGGGAGGGCCAUUACCCGAGCCCAGACCUCUAAUGGCAGAACCAAGAGGACCCAUGCUAGAUCAGAGGGGUCCACCCUUGGAUGGCAGAGGUGGAAGGGAUCCCCGAGGAAUAGAUGCACGAGGGAUGGAGGCCCGAGCCAUGGAGGCAAGAGGGUUAGAUGCCAGAGGAUUAGAGGCCCGUGCAAUGGAGGCCCGUGCGAUGGAAGCUCGUGCAAUGGAGGCCCGAGCGAUGGAGGCCCGUGCAAUGGAAGUCCGAGGGAUGGAGGCCAGAGGCAUGGAUACCAGAGGCCCAGUGCCUGGCCCCAGAGGACCUAUACCUAGUGGAAUGCAGGGUCCCAGUCCAAUUAACAUGGGGGCGGUUGUCCCCCAGGGAUCCAGACAGGUCCCAGUCAUGCAGGGAACAGGAAUGCAAGGAGCAAGUAUACAGGGUGGAAGCCAGCCUGGCGGCUUUAGUCCCGGGCAGAACCAAGUCACUCCACAGGAUCAUGAGAAGGCUGCUUUGAUUAUGCAGGUUCUACAACUGACUGCAGACCAGAUUGCCAUGUUGCCUCCUGAGCAAAGGCAGAGUAUCCUGAUUUUAAAGGAACAAAUACAGAAAUCCACUGGAGCACCUUGAUAGGUUUUCAAAAAUACCUGGCAAGAAAUCUGGAAAUUCUAUAAUUUUGUUGAAAUAUUGAAAAAAGAUGACCUGCAUCCUAACCCUUGAAUGACUCAAAUCAGUGCCAGGUGGAGGACUCCCAUCACCUUCUCUCAGAACAAAAUCACUUCAUUUUAUUGUCUUAGUUUGUAUAUUUUCUGUGACUUGAAAUAAACUUUGAACACAAUUUUAGUACACUGCAAAUUGAUACACAUGACCUUUUUGCUUUUAAAAAGCUUAACACUAAGGGUGAAACCUUAGAUGUGUUUUCUACCCUUACUGCAGUAUUGUACUUUAACAUAUUGCCAUAGUUUUGUUUUUAAGUUAACCACUUAUUCUUCUUGAUGAUAUUUGAGAAUUUCUCAGAAGCAAUGUUUUCUGGAACUUGGUUUUUGUUUAGUUUGCUUCCAGUAAGAAUUAUUAUAAGGCUUUGCCCUCUGAAAAUAUUCUAGCACUUCGGAGUCUUCUAGGAGAAAAUAUCACAUGCUUAGAGCUAUAAAAUGGUCAGAAGGCUAACAGAGCAAAGAGCCUAGCACAGCUGUGUGUUUAGUUUAGAAAAAUCCAAAUAUCAAAAUGCAUUUGUUUCAAUAGCAGGUCUGAACAUGUAUAAUUCAGAGUUAAGACAAAAAUUGUUUUAGCACUGGUUUGAGUGUGUCAGCAACACAAGAGACUGUUGACAUUUACUUGUGUGUUCUUAAACUUAUCAGUCUAGGCAGUCAACUUUGAAAGUUUAAAAAGCCACUGAUUUUUCACAUGCUCAAGAUGAAAUAAAAACAGAAAUCAAAUGAA